AGACCUGCACAAGGUGCUCAGGCUGGGCGGCCGCCUUCUGCCAGUGUCGGGGCCAUGCGAUGGGGCGUGGGGGGAGGGGCUGGGGAGAGUGCGACCCAGAGAGGUUCAGGAAGGACUUGGGGCCACCUGGCCCCUCGGUCGCGGAGACUGGGCGCACCGCCCUCCCCUCCGCCGCGCCCCGCGCGCCCCCGCCGCCUCUUCCGCCCUCUGGCCUUUUCCUCCUGGCCCGGCCUCCGCGUCCCGCCCGCAGCGUCCCCCAUUUCAACUUCCUGCUGCCCCGACACCCUGAACUUCUGGUCCUCCCCAUUCCUCAGCCCCACGCAGGACCACUUGGUUCUCCACACCAGGAACCAGAGCAGCUUGGCACCCCGGAGGGCAUGGGGGGCUCUCCCCUCCCUCCCAGUUCUCACAGGGGCUGUUCCGUCCCUCACCCUGAGCAAGACCAGACACCUCUGCAUUCGCAGCCCCCUGCUGUCCCCACAUGCUGCCUGGGGUCCAGCGCUCCGGAGCCCAUCCUCCCACCGACUACCCUCUUUGCUCCUGCACUUUUAUUUUUAUUUUAUUUUAUUUAUUUAUUUGAGACAGAGUCUCGCUCUGUCGCCCAGGCUGGAGUGUAAUGGCGCGAUCUCGGCUCACUGCAACCUCCGCCUCCCGGGUUCAGGCAAUUCUCCUGCCUCAGCCUCCCCAGUAGCUGGGACAACAGGCGUGUACCACCAUGCCCGGCUAAUUUUGUAUUUUUAGUAGAGACAGGGUUUCGCCAUGUUGGACAGGCUGGUCUUGAACUCCUGCCCUCAGGAGUUCCUCAGGAGGAGUUCUCGGCCUCUCAGAGUGCUGGGAUUACAGGCAUGAGCCACAGCGCCGGGCCUGCUACUGCACUUUUCAAGAAAUGGCUCAGGACUUCUCAUCUUAAACCAGAAACAACAAGGAAACCCAUUCUGUUGACUUUACAGCUUCUGUGUUGCUCUUCACAGCCCAAGUUUAUAAAAGAGACGCGUUUUCCGCCGUCUGCAUCUCCUCUUCUCACCCCUGCUCCCCACAGGAGGCCCUGAGCGCCCAGCAGCCCUUGGUCCUGCAUCCCCCUCCAGACAACUAAAGGGCCUGGCUCCCUCCACCCUGCCCGGAUCCAGCUCCCAGUGCCCGAAUCUAUCCCCCCUCCCCGGAUCCAUCCCCCCCUCCCCGGAUCCAUUCCCACUGCCUGAAUCUACUCUCCCCUGCCCGGCUCUAUUCCCCCUACCUGGAUCCAUUCCGUUGCCCAUGCCUGGUCCCUUCACCGGCUCUCUCCCCUGGGGCCGCAAACCUACCUGGGCCCCCCUCUGGCAGAAAGGGGUCCUCUCAGACCCACAGGUCCAACGGCUAAUCCUGGCUCUGCUUCCCCUGGGAGCCUUCUGCGGCUGCCCCCACCCUGGGCUGGAAUGAAUGGAACGCCUACUAUGAGGAGGUGGUGUACGUCCUAGAGGAGAUCGAGUACAUGAUCCAGAAGCUCCCUGAGUGGGCCGCGGAUGAGCCCGUGGAGAAGACGCCCCAGACUCAGCAGGACGAGCUCUACAUCCACUCGGAGCCACUGGGCGUGGUCCUCGUCAUUGGCACCUGGAACUACCCCUUCAACCUCACCAUCCAGCCCAUGGUGGGCGCCAUCGCUGCAGGGAACUCAGUGGUCCUCAAGCCCUCGGAGCUGAGUGAGAACAUGGCGAGCCUGCUGGCUACCAUCAUCCCCCAGUACCUGGACAAGGAUCUGUACCCAGUAAUCAAUGGGGGUGUCCCUGAGACCACGGAGCUGCUCAAGGAGAGGUUCGACCAUAUCCUGUACACGGGCAGCACGGGGGUGGGGAAGAUCAUCAUGACGGCUGCUGCCAAGCACCUGACCCCUGUCACGCUGGAGCUGGGAGGGAAGAGUCCCUGCUACGUGGACAAGAACUGUGACCUGGACGUGGCCUGCCGACGCAUCGCCUGGGGGAAAUUCAUGAACAGUGGCCAGACCUGCGUGGCCCCUGACUACAUCCUCUGUGACCCCUCGAUCCAGAACCAAAUUGUGGAGAAGCUCAAGAAGUCACUGAAAGAGUUCUACGGGGAAGAUGCUAAGAAAUCCCGGGACUAUGGAAGAAUCAUUAGUGCCCGGCACUUCCAGAGGGUGAUGGGCCUGAUUGAGGGCCAGAAGGUGGCUUAUGGGGGCACCGGGGAUGCCGCCACUCGCUACAUAGCCCCCACCAUCCUCACGGACGUGGACCCCCAGUCCCCGGUGAUGCAAGAGGAGAUCUUCGGGCCUGUGCUGCCCAUCGUGUGCGUGCGCAGCCUGGAGGAGGCCAUCCAGUUCAUCAACCAGCGUGAGAAGCCCCUGGCCCUCUACAUGUUCUCCAGCAACGACAAGGUGAUUAAGAAGAUGAUUGCAGAGACAUCCAGUGGUGGGGUGGCGGCCAACGAUGUCAUCGUCCACAUCACCUUGCACUCUCUGCCCUUCGGGGGCGUGGGGAACAGCGGCAUGGGAUCCUACCAUGGCAAGAAGAGCUUCGAGACUUUCUCUCACCGCCGCUCUUGCCUGGUGAGGCCUCUGAUGAAUGAUGAAGGCCUGAAGGUCAGAUACCCCCCGAGCCCGGCCAAGAUGACCCAGCACUGAGGAGGGGUUGCUCCGCCUGGCCUGGCCAUACUGUGUCCCAUCGGAGUGCGGACCACCCUCACUGGCUCUCCUGGCCCUGGGAGAAUCGCUCCUGCAGCCCCAGCCCAGCCCCACUCCUCUGCUGACCUGCUGACCUGUGCACACCCCACUCCCACAUGGGCCCAGGCCUCACCAUUCCAAGUCUCCACCCCUUUCUAGACCAAUAAAGAGACGAAUACAAUUUUCUAACUCAGCAAA